UAGUGUUGACAUCCCUGCCUGCGCUGGCGGUCCCACCCCCGACUCCCACCAAAACGGCACCUCCCGCGUUGGUCAAUGGGCUGGAGCUGUCAGAGCCGCGGAGCUGGCUGUACCUAGAAGAGAUGGUCAACUCCUUGCUCAACACAGCGCAGCAGCUGAAGACGCUGUUUGAGCAAGCCAAGCAUGCCAGCACCUACCGAGAAGCUGCCACAAACCAGGCCAAGAUCCACGCUGACGCAGAGCGGAAGGAGGUGAUCCACCCGCCUCGGCUGCCCAAAGUCCUGGGAUUACAGCAGUCCUGCGUUAACUGCGGCCGGGAGGCUAUGAGCGAGUGCACCGGCUGCCACAAGGUCAACUACUGCUCCACCUUCUGCCAACGCAAGGACUGGAAGGAUCACCAGCACAUAUGCGGCCAGUCAGCAGCUGUCACCGUCCAGGCAGACGAAGUCCACGUGGCUGAAAGCGUGAUGGAGAAGGUGACCGUGUGAGGCUCCAUCGGCCGCCCUGGGAGCUGGGGCCCCUCGCACUCCUGUGAGGCUUUUGCAGGUCGAAGGCCCCCCUGAGGACUCUGGGGGGACGUUGAGAAGAGGGGUGUGGGAAGGUAAAGAAACUUGCUGGACAAGUCAUUAACACACUUUAAGCGAAUGGUGCCCUGGGAAGCGCACUCCCCCUGCCCGGGCCCCCUGCCCGCUCGCGGACAGAUUUUUUAUCCCUGGGAUCAUGAGCGUCCGGUCUUGCCCACAGGGCCUGUGCUGCGACGCACAUACAUACGUGUUGUGUCUGUCAAUAAAGUGUAAAUAAGGUCUCCCUGCCCCACA